AGUCGCGCUGCUGUGGCGGCCGCUGUAGCAGCGGCGGUCCAGUCGUAGCCCGGCCGCCCGCGCCUGUCCGGUCCGGUCCGGCCACGGAGGCAGCGCAGCGGCGGGACUCCGAGCCUACCCCGCCGAGUGAGCUGCGCCGCACCGUGCCGUCCCACCCGGCACCCACCAGUCCGAUGGGGCCGCAGCGGCGGCUGUCCCCUGCCGGGGCCGCCCUACUCUGGGGCUUCCUGCUCCAGCUGACAGCCGCUCAGGAAGCAAUCUUGCAUGCGUCUGGAAAUGGCACAACCAAGGACUACUGCAUGCUUUAUAACCCUUAUUGGACAGCUCUUCCAAGUACCCUAGAAAAUGCAACUUCCAUUAGUUUGAUGAAUCUGACUUCCACACCACUAUGCAACCUUUCUGAUAUUCCUCCUGUUGGCAUAAAGAGCAAAGCAGUUGUGGUUCCAUGGGGAAGCUGCCAUUUUCUUGAAAAAGCCAGAAUUGCACAGAAAGGAGGUGCUGAAGCAAUGUUAGUUGUCAAUAACAGUGUCCUAUUUCCUCCCUCAGGUAACAGAUCUGAAUUUCCUGAUGUGAAAAUACUGAUUGCAUUUAUAAGCUACAAAGACUUUAGAGAUAUGAACCAGACUCUAGGAGAUAACAUUACUGUGAAAAUGUAUUCUCCAUCGUGGCCUAACUUUGAUUAUACUAUGGUGGUUAUUUUUGUAAUUGCGGUGUUCACUGUGGCAUUAGGUGGAUACUGGAGUGGACUAGUUGAAUUGGAAAACUUGAAAGCAGUGACAACUGAAGAUAGAGAAAUGAGGAAAAAGAAGGAAGAAUAUUUAACUUUUAGUCCUCUUACAGUUGUAAUAUUUGUGGUCAUCUGCUGUGUUAUGAUGGUCUUACUUUAUUUCUUCUACAAAUGGUUGGUUUAUGUUAUGAUAGCAAUUUUCUGCAUAGCAUCAGCAAUGAGUCUGUACAACUGUCUUGCUGCACUAAUUCAUAAGAUACCAUAUGGACAAUGCACGAUUGCAUGUCGUGGCAAAAACAUGGAAGUGAGACUUAUUUUUCUCUCUGGACUGUGCAUAGCAGUAGCUGUUGUUUGGGCUGUGUUUCGAAAUGAAGACAGGUGGGCUUGGAUUUUACAGGAUAUCUUGGGGAUUGCUUUCUGUCUGAAUUUAAUUAAAACACUGAAGUUGCCCAACUUCAAGUCAUGUGUGAUACUUCUAGGCCUUCUCCUCCUCUAUGAUGUAUUUUUUGUUUUCAUAACACCAUUCAUCACAAAGAAUGGUGAGAGUAUCAUGGUUGAACUCGCAGCUGGACCUUUUGGAAAUAAUGAAAAGAAUGAUGGAAACUUGGUGGAAGCCACUGGUCAACCCUCAGCUCCCCAUGAGAAAUUGCCAGUAGUCAUCAGAGUACCAAAACUGAUCUAUUUCUCAGUAAUGAGUGUGUGCCUCAUGCCUGUUUCAAUAUUGGGUUUUGGAGACAUUAUUGUACCAGGCCUGUUGAUUGCAUACUGUAGAAGAUUUGAUGUUCAGACUGGUUCUUCUUACAUAUACUAUGUUUCGUCUACAGUUGCCUAUGCUAUUGGCAUGAUACUUACAUUUGUUGUUCUGGUGCUGAUGAAAAAGGGGCAACCUGCUCUCCUCUAUUUAGUACCUUGCACACUUAUUACUGCCUCAGUUGUUGCCUGGAGACGUAAGGAAAUGAAAAAGUUCUGGAAAGGUAACAGCUAUCAGAUGAUGGACCAUUUGGAUUGUGCAACAAAUGAAGAAAACCCUGUGAUAUCUGGUGAACAGAUUGUCCAGCAAUAAUAUUAUGUGGAACUGCUAUAAUGUGUCAUUGAUUUUCUACAAAUAGACUUCGACUUUUUAAAUUGACUUUUGAAUUGACAAUCUGAAAGAGUCUUCAAUGAUAUGCUUGCAAAAAUAUAUUUUUAUGAGCUGGUACUGACAGUUACAUCAUAAAUAACUAAAACGCUUUGCUUUUAAUGUUAAAGUUGUGCCUUCACAUUAAAUAAAACAUAUGGUCUGUGUAGUUUCCGAGAUGUACUAUAUACAGUAUAUUUUUCUAAAAAAAAAUGCCUUGACCCACCCCUAUACUUUUUUUUAACGAAAUCUGUUUCUUUCAGCUCUGAUGGUAGAUACAAGUAGUUACUAUUUCUGAAUGGGUUUUACUGUAAAGAAUUAUGCAAAUUGGCCAGGCGCGGUGGCUCACGCCUGUAAUCCCAACACUUUGGGAGGCCAAGGCGGGCGGAUCACGAGGUCAGGAGAUCGAGACCAUCCUGGCUAACACGGUGAAACCCCUCUCUACUAAAAAUACCAAAAAUUAGCUGGGCGUGGUGGAGGGUGCCUGUAGUCCCAGCUACUGGGAAGGCUGAGACAGGAGAAUGGCGUGAACCCGGGAAGUGGAGCUUGCAGUGAGCCAAGAUCACGCCACUGCACUCCAGCCUGGGCGACAGAGUGAGACUCCAUCCCAAAAAAAAAGAUUUAUGCAAAUUAUAUCUGCUCUGUAGAAAUAACUGUUUAACACCAUGCAAGAAGGCGGUUCAACGGUGAAAAUUUGGACCUUAUAUCACUGCAGAGGUUAGAAAUACAUAAUUUUGGAAAUAUAAGUGCAUAUUUUUGUAGUAUUUUUUUAAACCCAAUCCUUUCAUAAACUUGAGAACUGAAAUUACUUCAGACUGCACGUGUAUUAUAUUAAGAACAUUUUUCCAGAUAUAGAGAAACAUAAUAUAUAGAACUAGUCACUAAAAGGAGACAGACACUGAAAUCUAGUUUUCAUUGGUUUGACAGCCUUUUUUUUUUAAAUGUAGCUUAAAUUUCAGUACUAACAUUCAGUUUCACUUUGGUAUUUCUGAUCUUUGCAAUUUGGUUCUGUUAAUGUUAAGGUUUGAUUUUUUAAAAAAAUUAUUUUUCUUAAGAAAUUAUGUAUUAAUACAUAUGGCUCAUCGUUGAAUACAGCAUUCCUAACAUUAUCCCACAUUCCCCCACUCCCACCCGUUAUCUUUUUUUCUUCCUGAUGCCCACCCCUUUUCCCAUAGGUAAUGAUUCUUAAUCUUGGUGGAGGAUGUACAAAGUGCGGUUCAGAGAAAAGAAUUGGCAACAACAGCAAGAGACUUGGUGUUAGUCUCAGUUUAAUUACAAUACAAGGAAGAGUUGAGUAAUUUGCCGCAUCUCAAGACCUUGUAUCUCAGUUUUCUUUUUUUUUUUUUUUUUUUUUUUGAGACGGAGUCUCGCUCUGUCGCCCAGGCUGGAGUGCAGUGGCGGGAUCUCGGCUCACUGCAAGCUCCGCCUCCCGGGUUCACGCCAUUCUCCUGCCUCAGCCUCCCAAGUAGCUAGGACUACAGGCGCCCGCCACUACGCCCGGCUAUUUUUUGUAGUUUUAGUAGAGACGGGGUUUCACCGUUUUAGCCGGGAUGGUCUCGAUCUCCUGACCUCGUGAUCCGCCCGCCUCGGCCUCCCAAAGUGCUGGGAUUACAGGCGUGAGCCACCGCGCCCGGCCAUAUCUCAGUUUUCUAAUCUGUAAAAUGAGUAGGUUAGACCAGCUAAUCACUCUGGUACCUUCCAACUUGAAAAAAGUUUUUUCCCCAUUCUUUGGUAAAUUUUAGAUGUGGCCUGAACAUUCUCCUGGAAGUCAGAGGUCAAAUUAUCUUUCCAUUUUCUUUUAUUUUAGUAAGAAUUUCGCAAAUGACAAGUGAUAACAAAGGCAGCAGGAUUUUUCAUUUCUCUGUAAAUAAUGUAUAAAAUAUGUGAACAGAACUAUAUCUUUCAUCUAAGGCCAGUUCAAUUUAUUAAAAAUAAAACUAAUGCCUUUUAAAAUUGAUCAGACCUUUGAUACUUGAACUAAAUUUUGCAUUAGAGACUUUUUAAAAAUUGUUCGCUUUUGCUGAAUAAAUUGCAAAUAGAGAAGCUUCAUUGACAGUCAGUCCCUCUCUGCUUAAUGCAGUUAUGGGUCCUUUCGUUUAUGGCAAAUGACUUACCUGACAAGAGUUAAUUUUGCCUCCAUUGUAUCAAGUUUGAAUAUUUUCCAAGAAAUCUGAUUUAUUUGGCAGACUCUGAGAGAGAGAACAGAUUAAGUGCCGUUUUAAAACUCUGUAUUUUCAUUUAUAAUAAUAAAAUAUUUGCCAAAAUACAGCUGUUUUGUAAAAUUAUCUGCACCCUCAUCCAAGCUUUAUAUUUAAUAGCCUUAAUCACAUUUUAUGAAGAAUGUUAAAGAAAAUUUUUUUUUUACUACAUCGAAAUGAGAUAAUUAAUUUCUUUUUUUUUUUUUUGGAAAUGGAGUCUCCCUCUGUCACCCAGGCUGGAGUGCAGUAGCAAGAUCUUGGCUCACUACAACCUCUGCCUCCUGGUUCAAGCAAUUUUCCUGCCUCAGCCUCCCAAGUAGACGGGAUUACAGGUGCGUGCCACCACACCUGGCUAAUUUUUGUAUUUUUAGUAGAGACGGGGUUUCACCUUGUUGGUCAGGCUGGUCUUGAGCUCCUGACCUCAUGAUCUGCCCGCCUCAGACUCCCCAAGUGCUGGGAUUGCAGGCAUGAGCCACCGCGCCUGGCAAAAUAAGAUAAUUUCUCAAAAUAAUUUGGUUUCAUAUAACUGGAGUAGUAAUUAAUAUUUUAACUUCAUCAACUAGAUGUAUCUCCUCAGUAGCAUAGUAACUGGUACAUCCAGAAAUCUGAAAUCCGAGUUACUUGAUACAAAUUCUACUUUAUCUAACCAUUAGUUAUUAAGGAGGUAAAAUCUUGUUCUAAUUUGCUAUUAAAAUCUUAUUGGUUAAAUAGAAAUAAGAAAAAGUAUAAUUAAGUUUCUUCAUCCUCAAUGUCAACUUUAUAUUGUAAUUAAAUGUGUAGCAACCAAGCUGACAAUAGUGAUUAAGAAAUUAAAGUACAGAAAUAUUUUAUUUGGGGACUCAAAAUGAACAAAAGAUAGAUAAGAUUAAAAUUUCACUUAAAAAGCUGCCAUCUCUUCCUCUCUUGCCCUCCCACCACCAAUAACUUUAAGGGGAAGAGAAGCUGGUUUUUUCCCUAAACAUGUCUUUAAAAUAAUGAUACACUGUAUUUAUUAAUUCUUGAUGCAAAAAAAAAAAAGUUAGAAAAUCCCUUUGAACAUUUUUGUGGCUUAUCAACAGAAAUCACUAUCUCAAAUUGUAAUGUAGAUUACUUUUGUCUCAGUUUAGUUUAGCAAAAAUAAAUGUGAGGCUUGUGGGGAAAGACCUUGAUAUUCUAAUACAUUAUAUUUUCUUCUAGCUUGUAGAUUUUUUUUUUUUUUUUUUUUUGAGACAGAGUUUCGCUCUUUUUGCCCAGGCUGGAGUGCAAUGGCAUGAUAUCAGCUCACUGCAAUCUCCGACUCCCGGGUUCAAGCAAUUCUCCUGACUCAGCCUCCUGAGUAGCUGGGAUUAUAGGCAUGUGCCACCACACCCGGCUAAUAUAGUAUUUUUAGUAGAGACGGGGUUUCUCCAUGUUGAUCAGGCUGGUCUCGAACUCCCAACCUGAGGUGAUCCGCCCGCCUCAGCCUCCUAAAGUGCUGGGAUUACAGGCAUGAGCCACCGUGCCUGGCACUUGUAGAUUUUUUUUUAGAUUAGCAAUUCCUUAGUAGAAUCUGCAAUUUAUUUCUCUUUUAAAGAGAAUUUUAACCCAUCUGCUAUUGGCAUUCUUAUAUUUUACUUGUCCAUAGAGAUUUUAGUGAAUUGAUACAUUUAUAAUAAAUACAAAUGAGCUUUCCAGUUUUCUUUGCUCUUUCAAUUUAUGCUUUAGUAUAAGCAAAAAUUACUAUUUUUACAUUUUUAAAAAUUGUGGGUACAUGUAGGUGUAUAUAUUUAUGGAGUGCAUGAGAUGUUUUGAUACAGGUAUGCAAUGUGAAAUAAGCGGAUCAUGGAGAAUGGGGUAUCCAUUCCCUCAAGCAUUUAUCCUUUGAGUUAUAGACAUAUUUUACAUUUGAAUAAAAAAUAUUUGAACUAAGGCCGGGUGCGGUGGCUCACACCUGUAAUCCCAGCACUUUGGGAGGCCAAGGCGGGUGGAUCAUGAGGUCAGGAGUUUGAGACCAGCCUGACCAACAUGGUGAAACCCCGUCUCUACUAAAAAUACAAAAAUUAGCUGGGUGUGGUGGGGCUCGCCUGUAACCCCAGCUACUCAGGAGACUGAGGCAGGAGAAUCGCUUGAACCUGGGAGGUGGAGGUUGCAGUGAGUCGAGAUCACACCACUGCACUCCAGCCUGGGCGACAGAGCGAGACUCCAUCUCAAAAAAAAAAAAAAAAAAAAAAAAUAUAUAUAUGUAUAUAUAUAUAUAUAUAUAUGUAUAUAUGAACUAAUUUAUUUAGGCUUAAUCUCUAAAAUUUCAGCCUGAUCUUAACCAAUGAAAUUUCAAAAACAAAAACUGUACUUCAGUCUACAAUUGAAUGGAAUUCAGUGUAGACCAGUACAAUGGAAUGUACUGGCUGAGAUGGGAGGGUCCCUUGAGCCCAGGAGUUUGAGGCUGUAGUGAGCUGUGAUUGUGUCUGUGAAUAGUGACUGCACUCCAGCCUAGGUGACAUAGCAAGAUGCCAUCUCAAAGAAAUAUAGAUAUAUAACAUAAAAUAAAUAACUUUAUACAUUUCCUGGAGGAAAAGUACUCUGUAAAUUCAAGAGAUCUGAAUCAAAUUACUCAACCUUUUGGAAUUUGAUCCUCUACUGUAAUACUCAUAUGCUAGAUUACUGAAUUUUCAGAGUGAAAAAAAAUUGACAGGGUAAUAUAUAGGCCAUAUUAUAGUGAAGAUCAUAAGUAUAAAUGUCCUCGUUUAAUCUUUCCAUAUUGAGGACAGCCUCUGCAUAUAAAAAUGUUCAUUGGGAGAAAAAUUAUUUUUAAAACUAAAUUUUUAUAGUAGUCCUCCAUUACUGGCAAUUAAGGAGCAACCCACAAAAUGUCAUUAUGUGGUUCUUUGAUUAGGCAUAAAAAGUAUUGCAAACAGCUUUUCUAUUCCUUUGGAAUAUGAAUCUUUUUAAUGUCUAAAGUUAACCUGCAACAUUUUCUAGUAGGACAAGUCAAUGUAAAUUAGGUAAUUUUUGCCUGUUUUAUACCUUCUGUUGCAUUUUGUUCAAAUGAAAACAUUUUUUAAAACAUGAUUGAAUUUUUACUUCUCAGAUAAUUGGUUUGAGUGUGGAAUUUCUUUUUUAACACUUUGAUAUGUAAGUUAGUGUAAAUUAAUACUUUUAUAACACUACUAGGCUUUAUAUUUUUAUGGAAUGUUUUAAAAUUUGAAAUUUUUGAAGUGUUAAUUUAGCAGUACUUUAUCAUUAUGUGCCAAUACUGACAAGAAAAACAAUUUUUUAUGUAUUUAAUAUACUAUGGUAUUCAAUAAAUUCUAUUUUAAAAUAAAA